GACAGCGGACCCAAGAUGGCGACCGAGUUGGAGUACGAGUCUGUGCUGUGUGUGAAGCCAGACGUCAGCGUCUACCGGAUUCCGCCCCGGGCCUCCAACCGCGGUUACAGGGCCUCUGACUGGAAAUUAGACCAGCCUGAUUGGACUGGUCGCCUCCGAAUCACUUCAAAAGGGAAGACUGCCUAUAUCAAACUCGAGGAUAAAGUUUCAGGGGAGCUCUUUGCUCAGGCACCAGUAGAACAAUAUCCUGGUAUUGCUGUGGAGACGGUGACAGAUUCUAGCCGCUACUUUGUAAUCCGGAUCCAGGAUGGUACUGGGCGCAGUGCUUUCAUUGGCAUUGGCUUCACAGAUCGGGGAGAUGCCUUCGACUUUAAUGUCUCCUUGCAGGAUCACUUCAAGUGGGUAAAGCAGGAAUCUGAGAUUUCCAAGGAAUCUCAAGAAAUGGAUGCUCGUCCUAAGUUGGAUCUGGGCUUCAAGGAAGGACAAACCAUCAAGUUGUGUAUCGGGAACAUUACAAACAAGAAAGGAGGUGCUUCUAAGCCCAGGACUGCAAGGGGUGGGGGUCUGAGCUUACUCCCACCCCCGCCAGGAGGCAAAGUCACUAUUCCCCCACCAUCCUCCUCAGUUGCCAUCAGCAAUCAUGUCACCCCACCACCCAUUCCGAAAUCUAACCAUGGAGGCAGUGAUGCAGAUAUCCUUUUAGAUUUGGAUUCUCCUGCUCCUGUCACGACACCAGCACCAACUCCAGUUUCUGUAAGCAAUGACUUGUGGGGAGACUUCAGCACUGCCUCCAGCUCUGUUCCAAACCAGGCACCACAGCCAUCCAACUGGGUCCAGUUCUGAAUGGCAUUGGCAGGACAUUAAGGACAGACUUGAGGAAUAAAAAUGACCUUGAGGGCACCAAUCUGUGAGGGAAGUUAGGAACCCAUUUCCUCCCCAGAACCAGAAUGACUGGACAAUCUUUUUCAUAGCUUCUCCAUCACAUUCAAGCUGGUUUAUGUCACUCCCCUGUGUUGUUACUUGUACAGCCAAGAAAGUAUCUGUUAUCUCCUGCGUAGUACCAAGGUAGGGGACUAGUGGAUCUUAUCAUAGUUUUGGCUGACUAUGCAGGGCUUAAAAGGCCAGCGUCUGUUUGAGGGGGAAUGACCUCUAACAUCUGUAAAAUUUGUCUCAUCUUUUAAUUUCUUUAACUUAUUUCAAAAUCAUCUCAUGACCCUUGUGUGCCUCUUUGUGAAGCCCUAUUUAGCAAUUUCAGGGGAGUCAAAAACCUUGCAACUUCCUUCUCCACUAACCCAGGACUAAAAAUGGACAGGCUGACCUCAGUGUUUACAAAUUCAGAAUUUUGAUAGGGGUAGAUAUGGAGAAAGACCUAUUUCCUGGGUCUCUGCUGUGUAGUCUCCUUCAGGCUUAUUGUGCUCAGUGAACAUCCAGUGCUGGGUGCAGCUCCAUCACCCUCUUGUGUGUUUACAUGUCUCUUUCUAUGAUAAGAGGGUUGUGUUGGUGGCACCUCCACUACUCUUUUCUGUUUGUUGAGUUUGAAUUGUGUUAACAUCUUUGAUCAGUGGGUGUAUCUGUAAUGAAGGAGGUUCAAGAGGCUGUGCUUUCCAAGUGAUAGUCUAUAGGAGUGUUUAAUUUCUUGCAGCUCCAUCUGGUUGCUGCAUUUGAAGCAUGGCAUUAAUUUGUAUUUGCCCUGUUCUUUGACCUAAAGUUGAAGGGUUUAGAGUUUUUAACCUGAUCUGUAGAGCAGAGAGGUUGAAAGCACUUAACUCUUGUUUAGUAUCCUCAUUGCCUUGCUGCCUGGGUAUCUGGCCCCUUUCCAUAAACAUUUCUUUUCAGUUCAUGUAGUUCUUUAAUAGAAAGCUGCUAUUAUGUAUAUUGUCAUUUGUGAAGGAAGUUGGAGAGUCACAGCUUUACUGUGACAGGUUUUGCCCAAGGCUUUGAUACCUGUCACCCAGGGUAUCUUAAAAGCAAGUUGUUCUCCCACUACUUUCCUUUCCCUCUGCCCUGCCAUUCCUAUUACAAUGCUGUGAAAAAAGUUCUGCUUCUUAGGUGAAUGGGUACUUUCUAUUUUGUUUCUAAACGAGCAAUUUUGAGGAUGAAAUGGGAAGAUAUCAUUGCUUCCUUUUUGCACCUAUUGGGUAUGUACACUCUGGCCGAAGGGAGUCCUUAUGUUUAGUUUCAAAAUAUAUUACUUUCCUGGAUUCUCUUCUUCACUUUUUCUGACUUUGGGUCCAUUUUCUUUUCAUUGCCUCCUUUUCCAGGCAGCUCUAUUCUUGCAGAGCCAUAGCAGGACAUGUUAAAAUUCCAAUAGAAAACACUAAAAGGAAAGUCUGUGGAAUCACUAGUGACUAAAUACUGGGAACCUAUUUUCUCAAUCUUCCUCCAUGUUGUGUUCUUUGUAUUCUUGAGAUGAUAAUAUAUUAUGUAUUUGAAUUCCUGAAAAAUGGAAAAUGUUUAAGAUAUAUGUAUAUAAAGUGUAUGCUGUAUUGGUGCAAUAAUGGUAAUUAAAAAUAUGAAAAAAGUGUCUCUUUUAUCUUUUAAUUUGCUUAUUUGAUUACCUUUUAAAUUUAAUUGACCAAAUAUAAGUGGACCAGUAGUUAAUAAAGGAUAUUUAUAUCACUCUUUAUUAAGAAA